AGUUGACAGCAAGUAGGAGGGCCCUAUGGAAGGAGAAAAAAAGACAACACGAGAAAAAUUAGUAUUUUCUACCUUCUGAAAUUAAUGGUCAUGAGUUCGUAUAUGGUGAACUCCAAGUAUGUGGACCCCAAGUUCCCUCCGUGCGAGGAGUAUUUGCAGGGCGGCUACCUAGGCGAGCAGGGCGCCGACUACUACGGCGGCGGCGCGCAGGGCGCAGACUUCCAGCCCCCGGGGCUCUACCCACGGCCCGACUUCGGUGAGCAGCCUUUCGGAGGCAGCGGCCCCGGGCCUGGCUCGGCGCUGCCUGCGCGGGGUCACGGACAAGAGCCAGGCGGCCCCGGCGGUCACUACGCCGCUCCAGGAGAGCCUUGCCCAGCUCCCCCGGCGCCUCCGCCGGCGCCCCUGCCUGGCGCCCGGGCCUACAGUCAGUCCGACCCCAAGCAGCCGCCCUCCGGGACGGCACUCAAGCAGCCGGCCGUGGUCUACCCCUGGAUGAAGAAGGUGCACGUGAAUUCGGUGAACCCCAACUACACCGGUGGGGAACCCAAGCGGUCCCGAACGGCCUACACCCGGCAGCAAGUCCUAGAACUGGAAAAAGAAUUUCAUUUUAACAGGUAUCUGACAAGGCGCCGUCGGAUUGAAAUCGCUCACACCCUGUGUCUGUCGGAGCGCCAGAUCAAGAUCUGGUUCCAGAACCGGAGGAUGAAGUGGAAAAAAGAUCAUAAGCUGCCCAACACUAAAGGCAGGUCAUCGUCCUCAUCUUCCUCCUCAUCUUGCUCCUCCUCAGUCGCCCCCAGCCAGCAUUUACAGCCGAUGGCCAAAGACCACCACACGGACCUGACGACCUUAUAGAAGUGGGGACCCUGGGCCCAUCUCUCCCUGCGCACCAGGCUGAGCCGAAGCUGCGGGGGCAGGCCGGGCCUGCUGUCACCUCGCUGGGCUCUAAGGUACUGUGGGGUGGACCUGGGACAAGCAGGCCGCCCUCGGACUAGGUUAGCAUCCUGCCCGAGGGCAGCCCCCUCCCUAGAGCGGGAUGGGGAUGGGAGGGGGGGCGGGAUUCUCUCUCUAAGUAUAUUAUAUGGCAGGAGCUACUGAGAACAUAAAAUCUUGGCGAGUCAUUAAACUUAUGAAAAUCA